GGCAGGAGCUACCCUUCCCGUGGCCCCGGACCUUGGGUGGGCUGUGGGCUCAGGGAGCGGAGGGGAGGCCUUAAGCAUCCACUCUCUGCCCGGUGUUUUUGUUCUCAUCAGGGAGCCUCAGAUGGGAAGGGACUCGAGCCCCACCUGUCCCUGGACUCUGGAAUGCCACGGAAUUAACCCGAGCAGGCAUGGAGGCCUCUGCUCUCACCUCAUCAGCAGUGACCAGUGUGGCCAAAGUGGUCAGGGUGGCCUCUGGCUCUGCCGUAGUUUUGCCCCUGGCCAGGAUUGCUACAGUUGUGAUUGGAGGAGUUGUGGCCAUGGCGGCUGUGCCCAUGGUGCUCAGUGCCAUGGGCUUCACUGCGGCGGGAAUCGCCUCGUCCUCCAUAGCAGCCAAGAUGAUGUCCGCGGCGGCCAUUGCCAAUGGGGGUGGAGUUGCCUCGGGCAGCCUUGUGGCUACUCUGCAGUCACUGGGAGCAACUGGACUCUCCGGAUUGACCAAGUUCAUCCUGGGCUCCAUUGGGUCUGCCAUUGCGGCUGUCAUUGCGAGGUUCUACUAGCUCCCUGCCCCUCGCCCUGCAGAGAAGAGAACCAUGCCAGGGGAGAAGGCACCCAGCCAUCCUGACCCAGCGAGGAGCCAACUAUCCCAAAUAUACCUGGGGUGAAAUAUACCAAAUUCUGCAUCUCCAGAGGAAAAUAAGAAAUAAAGAUGAAUUGUUGCAA